CUUACAGCGCCUGCCUCUUUCUGAGCGGCAUGAAGCCACCUCCCAGGCGGCGAGCGGCCCCGGCGCGCUAUCUGGGCGAGGUGACCGGUCCCGCGACCUGGAGCGCUCGCGAGAAGCGGCAGCUAGUGCGACUCCUGCAGGCGCGGCAGGGCCAGCCGGAGCCGGACGCCACCGAGCUGGCCCGGGAGCUGCGGGGCCGGAGCGAGGCUGAGAUCCGGGUCUUCCUCCAGCAGCUCAAGGGCCGCGUAGCCCGGGAGGCCAUUCAGAAAGUGCAUCCGGGUGGCCUUCAGGGACCAAGGCGCCGGGAGGCACAGCCCCCAGCCCCCAUAGAGGUCUGGACGGAUCUGGCUGAGAAGAUAACAGGGCCACUGGAAGAAGCCCUGGCAGUGGCUUUCUCGCAGGUGCUCACCAUCGCGGCCACGGAACCGGUCACCCUCCUGCACUCCAAGCCCCCCAAGCCCACGCAGGCCCGUGGAAAGCCUUUGCUCCUGAGCGCCCCUGGAGGACAGGAAGACCCCGCCCCUGAAAUACCUAGCUCUGCCCCUGCUGCACCUAGCUCCGCACCCAGGACUCCUGACCCUGCCCCUGAGAAACCUUCUGAGUCGUCGGCUGGUCCCUCCACUGAAGAAGACUUUGCUGUGGACUUUGAGAAGAUCUACAAGUACUUGUCCUCUGUCUCCCGAAGUGGCCGCAGCCCCGAGCUCUCAGCAGCUGAGUCCGCUGUGGUCCUCGACCUGCUCAUGUCACUUCCAGAGGAGCUGCCACUCCUGCCCUGCACAGCCCUGGUUGAGCAUAUGACGGAGACGUACCUACGCCUGACAGCCCCCCAGCCCAUUCCCGCUGGAGGGAGCCUGGGGCCUGCAGCAGAAGGGGAUGGGGCUGGCUCCAAGGCACCAGAGGAGACCCCCCCAGCCACCGAGAAGGCCGAGCACAGCGAACUGAAAUCGCCUUGGCAAGCAGCUGGGAUCUGUCCCCUGAACCCGUUCCUGGUGCCCCUGGAGCUUCUGGGUCGGGCAGCCACCCCUGCCAGGUGAGGGGCAUGGCGGGCAGGAGGCCACACCAGGCCCCCCGCCCUGCCCCUCGGUUCUGCUCGGCUGGCCCUGGCUCUUUCUGAGGAUCCCGUCAUGGGGGAAGGUCCUUGAGAUGAUGCUCAGCUGUGGGGCGGGCCUCUAAGAUGCCCCAUACUUUGGGGGUCUCAGAAAUGGAACCCCCGUUGUACAGGGGUUGGGUGGGGGUUGCAGGACUCCACUCACAAGCCUCCUGAUGUCAAGGACAGGCGGACAGGGCUGGCCUCCCCCAGUCCCCAAGCCCCACUGUGCCUUGUUGUCUGCUGGGGGGCCAUAGCUGGCACUGCCCACCGUAAAGGCCCUCGCACAUUUUCCCCCUUCCUGUACACCUCGGGGCCAGCAUCCUCACCUUCUUCAACUGACCAGUCGUGGUUACUCCCUGCUGCCAGGUCCUUCCCCUUCCCGGGGGUAUUCUGUGACCAUGAAUAAAGUUAUCAUUCUCUUUCUCUUUCA